GGGCGCCUCCAGCUCCGGCUCGGGCUCCGGCUCCGGCUCCGGGCGCCGACCAGGUCCCCUUGGCCCCCGCCGCGCGCCCUCCAACCUGCUGCUGCCGCCGCCGCGCCCCCCAGGCUCUGCCAGCUACCCGCGCUCUGAGCCCGGGGCCAGAUUCCCAUGGAAGCGCCGCGAUGUUCGCCCCCCGGCUGCUGGAUUUCCAGAAGACGAAAUACGCGAGGUUCAUGAACCACCGAGUCCCUGCCCACAAGAGGUACCAGCCCACAGAGUAUGAACAUGCGGCCAACUGUGCCACCCAUGCUUUCUGGAUCAUCCCCAGCAUCCUGGGCAGCUCCAACCUCUACUUCCUGUCGGACGAUGACUGGGAGACCAUCUCUGCCUGGAUCUACGGCCUCGGCCUCUGCGGCCUCUUCGUGGUGUCCACUGUGUUUCACACCAUCUCCUGGAAGAAGAGCCACCUCAGGAUGGUGGAACACUGUCUACACAUGUUCGACCGGAUGGUCAUCUAUUUCUUCAUAGCGGCUUCCUACGCACCCUGGCUGAACCUUCGGGAGCUGGGCCCCUGGGCCUCCCACAUGCGCUGGCUGGUCUGGAUUAUGGCUUCCGUGGGCACCAUCUAUGUCUUCUUCUUCCAUGAGCGAACAGGGAGCUGUGUGCAGUUUCUUCGUGGGGAGGCAUGUCCUAAGGCCGGCACGGCUUGUCUUCCUGCCAGGUACAAGCUUGUGGAGCUUCUCUGCUACGUCGUAAUGGGCUUCUUCCCCGCCCUGGUCAUCCUCUCCAUGCCCAACACCGAGGGCAUCUGGGAGCUGGUGACCGGAGGGGUCUUCUACUGCCUGGGCAUGGUCUUCUUCAAGAGUGACGGGAGGAUCCCCUUUGCCCACGCCAUCUGGCAUCUCUUUGUAGCAUUUGGUGCUGGUACCCACUACUAUGCCAUCUGGAGGUACCUCUAUCUGCCCAGCACCCUGCAGACCAAGGUGUCCAAAUGAGGUGACCCAGACUUGAGAGGUCGUUUGGGCUUUAGGAGUGGAGCACGUUUCUGUGAACGUUAACCCAGAGCACAGCGCCAAGGCCUGUCUUCCCUUUAUUGGGUAGAGUUCUUGAUGGCUCCAAGGUGACUUCUGGUGACAGCCAGAUCAUCCCUCGAGUCCCCAGCGAGAAAGAAAGCAUUUAGCCAUUCUUACAGAGGAGAAAUUAACCCUGUAAUGUGUUUCUAUUUUAGAUGAGUGUUUCCUAAUACAAGCAACAUUAACAUCUUCAGAAAAGGAAGCAGGCAUGGUCCUGGAAAAUUGGGGAAUGACGGGCCAAUCUGUGUUUCCUAAGGUCCUGAAGAAUCUGGCAAAGAGUCCUGUGGGUUGUUUAUACCUGGGUGGCCAGGGCCUCCCUCUCUGUUACCAAAGUCCAGGCUGGCGAAUUGUCUCUGGUUCAGGGAAAGGGGACAGCCCAGCUUGAAGAUGAGGGAUGGUGAAUGGCUGUGACCAUGGCAGACAUCACCAAUCAAGUGCAGCACAUGGGUGAUGUCAGAAUUCUUCCCAGCACAGUGUUCUGGGCAGCCAGUACCAAUCAAUUUGGCACUCAUGAUGGGACCUCUUUGCCCUUCCUGUCUGGUGUGCUCUGAAAUGGGAUAAUGGCCAGAGUAGCUGAAAAUCUCCAAAUGGGCAUUUGCAUGCCUAUCUCCUCAUCUCCCCCUCCCUUUUGGGAAACUCCUGGAGUAGGCAGUUUGGGGGCGGUAGAGGGAAACUGAGGCGCACACCCAUGCAGCCCCUGAUGUUCUGUUCCACCGUAGUUGAUUCUCAGUAGAGUUGGGAAUGAGGAUGCUGUUACUUGGCCAUUUCUUCCCAUCUCCAAAAAUCCAGAGACAUUACGAGAGCUAUUCAUUCAUAAGAUGGGGCAAACAGCCCCCAGGCACUUGCUCCCUGCUCCAUACUUAAGGUUUGUGAUGCCAACAUUUGGAUUCUCUCUUGGUGCCAAUCAGUGGCUGUUAGAGGCUACUCAGGUGUACCCCAAACAGAAGGCACAUGGAUCUGGGGCGACUGUUCCAGGUCCUCCCAACCUCUGAAGUGCUCAGUAGCCCAACAACAAGGCUGCUGGGGGCCUGUUCUUCAGCCCCCGUCAGGGCGGGGCCAGCCUCUCUGUCCAAUGCUGCCUGGACAUUUACUGGGGAGGUGAGUAGCAGGCCCAGCUCCAGGAUCUGAAUUGGAAUCUCAGAUUCUCUGGAUAAAGAAUCUGUCUCAAGUCAGGAGGUCCUCAUUCUGCGACUCCCAACCAGGGUGGAGUGGGCACAGACAGGAUGCCUUAUGCUUAUCUCUAGCACAUUCCAGGGGGUUCCAGGGUUCCUGCACCUGGAAUCCAGUGUGUCCAAGCCAGUAUUAAAUUAUCUCAACACA